CAAACCUUUUCUCCAUGGUGGAAGUCAUCAGAGAAAACUGUUAAUAGCACGUUAAUUUAGACUUUUAGAAUAUAUCCUGUCCCCACUGACAGCCUUUUUUGUUAUUAAAUAGAGUAUUCCUAACAACCCAACCCACCCUAUGGUCCCCUUCUCAGAAUAAUGUUUUAAAUACAUACACAUAUCAUUGUCUGUUAAUAAGGAACUGGGGAGGUGGUUCCAGAGUUACUGGAACAGAUUCAAAGACAGUUGCUGAAACUAUGUCCUGGUUGUUGCUUACUCUCCUCUAGAAAGAAGUACUUCCUCACUAAUCUGGCUUUCAGCCUCAGAUCUGCCCCAUUUUAACUGCUGCUACUAACAUUCUUCCUCUAUAGGCAGCAGGUUCUUCCUCCUUUCAGACAACAGUCACAGAGACACGUACUUACAUGAGCUUGAAAGAAGGGAAAUUCCUUAUUCCUGUGGGCAGAAACCAGGUGAAUUGUUAGAACUUUGGUUUAUCGACUUGGGCAUAGAGGGAUUCAGGGUACAUAAUGCUUGUUAAGGAAGAAUGGCAACUGUUGGGCUGUCUUACAGCCAACCCCCUCCUACAGUCUGUCAUGCCAGGCUUAGACCCAUGCAGACACAACAGGAAAAGUCUCAGAUUUUUCUUGGCUGCCAUAAAAGAUCAUUAGCCCUUUCAGAGGGAUUUCUCUGUGACAAACUGUUCUGGGAAGCAAUUGAUGAGGAUUGAGUAGUUGUCAGGCUCUUAGUGCCACAGAGUUGGUUAAUACUGUCAAAGGUGACCCACUGGAGAAAGAGAAACUUGGGAGAGGCAAUCUGCCAUGAGCCCUGAAUGUUCCUGCAUGUAUAUUCUUGCCUCAUGUGAAUGUAAGACUGACCAUUCUUCUUGGGCUGUACCUCAGUGUUCUGUUAGCAGUAAGCUACCUUGAAAUGAGCAAAUUUGCCUGUUGCUCACUGUAAAAGUUUUGAGCACCCCUCCCCUCACAAGCUGGGGGUCUGCAUAUGUAGUCAUCCAUCUAGGCCUACCCUGUGGCACUUGGGGGUGUAGGCCAUGGGCAGCUGGUGCAAACAUCAUGCUCAUGUUGCUGGCUAUACCAUAAGUAAUAAAGUUAUUUGUCUCUGACCCAGGAAUCUCAUGUCUUCUGGCAACAUCCAUGAAAGCAUCGCAGGCUAACUUGUUAGCUUACAAGUAGGAUAAAAUUCACAGAUGUGAAAAUUUUAGUAAUGAAAAUUGGAUCCUGACCAACAUGGUUUUCUAGAAGAGAAAGGACAAAGGCCUUUCAUGGGCUGGAUUAGGGGAUAAAAGAAAUUUGCUGGGAUCUGGUAGCAAGUCAGAUAUUCCCAAGUGAGGGAGGAGGAAAGAGUCCUGAGAAAAGUCCUACCUGAAGAAAGAGUCCUACCUGAGAAUAUUUUGAGGCUAAGGAGCAAGAGGUAGGAUUGAAACAUGCUGCCCAGAUUGUACUUAGGUUGUUGCUCAGUCUCUAGGCAGGAGGCAGAAAAGAUGUUUUGACAAUGAGGCAGCAAGCUCAUGGCUCCAGCUGAAAGGCAGUAUGGCCAUGGCUGAUGAAUGAUUUCCCAAAGAUGAAAUAAAUGAUGGCAGUGAUAAGGAUAUAGAACUUUGAACUAAAAACAUUAGCUGUUUGUUGAGUCCAAGUAGGUAGCCACUUGAAUUGAAAGUAAAUACAUGGCCUUGCUGACUGACACAAAGCCGUUCUCCUUAUGGCCUACACCCCCAAAAGUGCCACAAGGUAGUCCUAGAUGAAUGCCUACACAUGCAGACCCCAAGUUUGGUAGUGGGGGUGGAGUGCUUAAAACUUACAGUGAGCAAUAGGUAAACCUGCUCAUUUCAAGGUAGCUUACUGCCAACAGAACACUGAGGUACAGCCCAAGAAGAAUGGUCACGGCCUUAAAUUCAUAUGAAGGAAGAAAAUACAUGCAGGAACACUCAGCGUUCCUGGCAGAUUGCCUCUCCCAACAGUGUCUCCAGUGGGUCACCUUCGACAGUUUUAUCAACCUACUCUAGAACUUCUGAUCCCUCUCUCUCUACAGCUUUAAGGAAAAAAAGCUCCCCAUCUUUGGGGAAGGGAGGAAUGCCCCUUUUACAGCUCCGUUCAAUAUAGGCAUCCAAAUCACUAUCCUCCUUGGCCCCAUGGGGACAGGGAAAUCUGCACAUAGAGGUGGUCAAAAAUGCCAAAUACCAUGGGGCAGAUCUACAAUAGCAUGCAGGAGAGCAGCGAAAAAAAAGGAGCCCUGAGCCCUGGGGGUGCUUGUCAGAGCCAACAGGUAUUUGAAGGAAGAGGCAACACUGUUCUGGGGCAAGGAGUCAAAGUGGGAUUACUUCCUAGUAACAACUGUCUCCUGCAGGCUAGCCUCUUCCACCUCCUCCUUCCACCACCUCUCACACUUCUGGCUGUGGAAAUAACAUCAUUUCUUGGCUGUGAUCUCCAACAUACCUAUCUUAAACUGCUUGGUUUGGGUGCCCAUAGGGGAGAAAAAGUACCUGAAUUCAACUGGUAGGGUCUGUUAGCUUACAAGUAGGAUAAAAUUCACAGAUGUGAAAGUUGUGGUAAUGAAAAUUGGAUCCUGACCAACAUGGUUUUCUAGAAGAGAAAGGACAAAGGCCUUUCACGGGCUGGUUUAGGGGAUAAUUGCAUGGGAAAGGAAAAUUAAAAUGACCUGUGGAUGGAGCCUCUAAACAUUUAAUGUACUGCUGUUUUAUGGCUUUAGCAUCAAAGUGUGUUGUUAAUACCAAUAUACAUUUAAUUGAACUAGGAAAGUUUAUAAGUCUCCCAUUCAGGGACUACUGCAGUAUAGAGAGAUGUAGUCUAAAAGAAACAACAUACAACCGCAAGAGGAAAAGAAAUAAAAGCACAGGUUUAGUUGAAAACUUAGUUACUCCUGUAGUACUCAGGCCAUUUUCCAUUAUAACCAGCUAUGUGGACUUUGCAGUCACCAAGGUGAAAUAUCCUGAGUACUCCAAGAGUGACCUUUAAAAAGAUAGGCACCUCUUAGGCUGCUACUGAGCUCUUGAGGAAACAACAGCGGCCAGAGGAGCUUCCUGAAAGCGUAACUGAUUCAUUUAUGCAUACUGCAGGCAGUUAUCACUAUCCUGAGAGUCAUCCUAUUGGAAAUGUUGAUAAGGAAUUUGUUCUUGACUUUAGCUGCAGUCAUCAGUGACACCACCUCAGCUCUGGAUGGCACUUAAGUCAGCCUCAAUUCAUUGGCCAGGGUGGUUAUGGGUGAUAGAAUUGCUCUUCCUCUUUGUGGGCCAAAUUGGAGUCAGUGCAAUCACUAAUACAUCCCACUGUGACUGGAUUAAUGUCUCAGACCGAGUACAGGGUCAAUACAGAAACUUGAGAAUGCCACUUGGCUUUCUAAGGUAGAUCCUGAUGGUUUAUGAUUGUUGGUUUUUUUUUCCUACCUUGUUGGAUACAGGCCCUUGGAUAUGGCUGAAGUCAGUACUGAUUGGUCUUAUCCUGUUACAUAGAGUUCUGUUGAUAGUACCUUUAAUUAAAUGUAAUAAAAUACUUUGAAUGGACCUGGUUCCAGUUUCUGUCAGUUUAAUUAGAGUGACAGGUGGAGUGGCAUACUUAUGGGAGAAUUCAUCAAAAGCCAAGAUGGCAUAGAAAUGAAAGGUGCAUAUCGUUGGGAGACAAUUCUUCAUGGGUCUCUAGCAUUUCUGCAUAUUUUGCAAAGAGAGGCACUGACUAUCUUUGUUCCAGACUAUUUGUCCAGGAAUGUUUGUAUAGUAAACAACCUUAGAAGGUAUCAGAGCAAAGGGCGCACAUGCUCACUGCCCAUUAUUGAAGAUUCAGGUUCCCUAACCUCAAAGUUCCUCUCCUUUAAGGCACUUCAUUACAUGUGCAGGUAUCAUCUGGCUCUCUGCGUCAUCAUAUGGGAAUUGGGGCUCAGAACUGGAACAAAUGCUGGUACUCUGGCUACUGCUAUUGCUUCUCCCCAGCCUUGGGGCCGGUGCCUCUUCCGGGCUUCGGCGAAUGAGACCUGCGGACCUGCCCCCGCGCCCCAUGGAAGAAUCCCCGGCGUCCAGCUCUGCCCCGACAGAGACGGAGGAGCCGGGGUCCAGUGCAGAGGUCAUGGAAGAAGUGACAACAUGCUCCUUCAACAGCCCUCUGUUCCGGCAGGAAGAUGACAGAGGGAUUACCUACCGGAUCCCAGCCCUGCUCUACAUACCCCCCACCCACACCUUCCUGGCCUUUGCAGAGAAGCGUUCUACGAGGAGAGAUGAGGAUGCUCUCCACCUGGUGCUGAGGCGAGGGUUGAGGAUUGGGCAGUUGGUACAGUGGGGGCCCCUGAAGCCACUGAUGGAAGCCACACUACCGGGGCAUCGGACCAUGAACCCCUGUCCUGUAUGGGAGCAGAAGAGUGGUUGUGUGUUCCUGUUCUUCAUCUGUGUGCGGGGCCAUGUCACAGAGCGUCAACAGAUUGUGUCAGGCAGGAAUGCUGCCCGCCUUUGCUUCAUCUACAGUCAGGAUGCUGGAUGUUCAUGGAGUGAGGUGAGGGACUUGACUGAGGAGGUCAUUGGCUCAGAGCUGAAGCACUGGGCCACAUUUGCUGUGGGCCCAGGUCAUGGCAUCCAGCUGCAGUCAGGGAGACUGGUCAUCCCUGCGUAUACCUACUACAUCCCUUCCUGGUUCUUUUGCUUCCAGCUACCAUGUAAAACCAGGCCUCAUUCUCUGAUGAUCUACAGUGAUGACCUAGGGGUCACAUGGCACCAUGGUAGACUCAUUAGGCCCAUGGUUACAGUAGAAUGUGAAGUGGCAGAGGUGACUGGGAGGGCUGGCCACCCUGUGCUAUAUUGCAGUGCCCGGACACCAAACAGGUGCCGGGCAGAGGCGCUCAGCACUGACCAUGGUGAAGGCUUUCAGAGACUGGCCCUGAGUCGACAGCUCUGUGAGCCCCCACAUGGUUGCCAAGGGAGUGUGGUAAGUUUCCGGCCCCUGGAGAUCCCACAUAGGUGCCAGGACUCUAGCAGCAAAGAUGCACCCACCAUUCAGCAGAGCUCUCCAGGCAGUUCACUGAGGCUGGAGGAGGAAGCUGGAACACCGUCAGAAUCAUGGCUCUUGUACUCACACCCAACCAGUAGGAAACAGAGGGUUGACCUAGGUAUCUAUCUCAACCAGACCCCCUUGGAGGCUGCCUGCUGGUCCCGCCCCUGGAUCUUGCACUGUGGGCCCUGUGGCUACUCUGAUCUGGCUGCUCUGGAGGAGGAGGGCUUGUUUGGGUGUUUGUUUGAAUGUGGGACCAAGCAAGAGUGUGAGCAGAUUGCCUUCCGCCUGUUUACACACCGGGAGAUCCUGAGUCACCUGCAGGGGGACUGCACCAGCCCUGGUAGGAACCCAAGCCAAUUCAAAAGCAAUUAAUUGGCUUAGGACCCAAUUUCCAUAGAUGCAAAUGGCAGUUACAGACAGGUUAACAGAAGCUACUGAAGUCUACAGAUAAUCAAAAAACUUAAUAUUCUGUUCCCUACCUUUUUUCACUUUUCCUCCUCCAAAGAGCAAAAUGAAAAUUUUGCCUUAGCUACUGCAGUGGAAAGAGCACUGAACUAGGAGUUGGAAGACAAGGAUGUGGUCCUGGCUCUGCCACUGGCUUGCUUUUGGACCUUGGAUGUGUCACCUGAACUCUCUGGACCUCAGGUUUCCAUCUGUAAAAUGAGAGUAUUGGUUCUAAGAUUUCUCAUCUUCUCAUCCCUAGGACAAGCAUAGUGCCUGCAUGCUUCAUGAUCAGUAAGUCCUGGCUGCAUAAAGGACUCUGAUGUCAAAAUGGAAACCAGGGGACUUACCUUUUCACAUGACUUACCCCUCAUCCGAGUGUGAGGUUACAAGCAGGUGUCAUGGCAGGAAGGAAGACCAGAUCUGUAUGAUUUGUUCCAUUUUUAAUAACAAAAAUAUCCACACCCUUUUAAUAAUGCUCAGUUCUGUAGGCUCUCUAUCCUAGAGGAAUUGAGCAAAACAGAAGAAUCAUGAAGUCUCCUACCUUCUACAGCCUUGUAGUUCUGCUUACCUUCUCUUCCUCAUCCAGAAAGCAUCAUUUUCUAGGGAGAACAAUGAGAAUCUCAAUGCCAGUAGUACUGGAUAAUAGUGCGUAUUGCUUCUGGUGGCAUUACCCUGAUGAUGGGCUGAAGUUCAUUUAUUAGGGUGGUUCCUGAUGGGAAAAGGACAUGGAUUAGGACUUUAAAACACUGGACAGAAUUUCCCACAGUCUUUGCCCUCAAGGAGUUCACCAGUUUAUGGGGCUAGAAGAGCGAGAAAAUUCAAGAAAAUAAAUGUAGCUGGUGGGAGACUUUGUAGAUGUUGGGCUAUAUGUUGGGGUGAUGGUAGCUCCUGAUGUAAUUUUCUUAGUUGCAUCUUCAAUAUGCCUGGAGUCGUCUGUCCAAGGCUUGUCCAGGCUUCUGGGUUUCUCUCAAGUUUGUUUUUCUCAGGAUAUUGUCCUGGCCCAGCUACUCCUUUACCUGUGAGAAGAUCUUCACCAUUAGGAAGAUCUCUAGACCCCCAGAUCUCAGAAUCAGGCCUAUUUGUGUAGGCCCAUGGAAAUCACUACUUGUGAAGUAGAGAUGCCUUUUUGUCUAAUGGUUUUCGUGCUGAACUUAGUUCAUGCUGAGUCUCUCAGAUGAUACCACGUUGGUUGUUCCUAUCUUAGAUUGUUUCUCCCAUAGCCUGUUAUUGCAACAGAAAUUCUAUCAUGAGAGAUUUAUUUUUUUGUCCCUAUUUUAGGAGUCUAAUGCUUAAACUGGUAUCAACUAAAUAUAUUUGGUGUUGUACAAUGACCACAGAGAACAAGUCUUAGUCAUGAAAUAUAGCCUAGGAGACUAGGGGUUACAGUUGCACUAGUUGGGUAGAGAGAGUCCUACAGGAUAAAAGUGGAGAUUAACUUUACCUACUUUAGCAGAUUGCUUAAGCCAUGGCUUAGAGUGGCUUUUAAAAAUCCCCUUAGCCUCUCCUACAUUUGCCAAGGUAAUCUUCCCAAUACACAAUUAUUCACUCAUGUAUACAUUUAUCUAAAUAUUUCUUGAGUGCCUAAUACAAGGUACUUUCUACUGCCAUUCCUUGGCUCUAAAUCAUUUGUGGUUCUCCAUUGCCUAUUAUAAUGUAAAGAUGUUUACAUUUAGCCUGGCAUGUAGGACCUUCCAGCUGUUGGGUGAAAUAAUGCACACUUUCCUCUACUUCCUUAUAUGAGGCCCACUGUCAGGGAAAACCUCUGUCAAGUUGGCAGGUGGAGGGUGGUGGAGGUCUAGGGAUGGGCAGGAUUGGUGCAGGGAGGAAUUGGGGAAGGGGAGAGGAUUAAAAGGGCAGCCCCCUCCUGAGUGGUAGAAACUCCUUGUUUAGCAAAGCUUUCCUGAACACUGUACUGCAAGUGGAUAGGAAUAGGGAGGAUGGCCAAGUCGUACAACCAGGGCUAAAGGAUGAAAAGAAUGAGAAUAUCAACUUCUUUUUUUUUUUUUUUGAGACAGAAUCUCACUCUGUCGCCCAGGCUGGAGUACAGUGGCACAAUCUCAGCUCACUGCAGUCUCCGCCUCCUGGGUUCAAGCAAUUCUCCUGCCUCAGCCUCCCAAGUAGCUGGGAUUACAGGUGCCUGCCACUACGCCCAGCUAAUUUUUUGUAUUUUUAGUAGAGACGGGGUUUCACCAUGUUGGCCAGGCUUGUCUCGAACUCCUAGCCUUGUGAUUCGCCUGCCUCGGCCUCCCAAAGUGCUGGGAAUACAGGCAUGAGCUACUGCGCCCAGCCGAGAAUAUCAACUUCUUUAGGACUACUCAAGAAGGGAGUCAAGGCAGGGACCUUGGUCUGUGCCACUGUGACGCAGAGAUGUAUAAUACCAGUACUCAUAAGAGGUCCAUCUCUAAAUUGCCCUCCUCUUACUUCUUCCCCCUGCCUCAUGUUUUUUCUCUUUAAUGACUAGCAUCGAAACUCUUUAAAUGGGGCAGGCCUGUGUUCUUAUCUCAGGAAUAGUAAGAAAAGGGGGUUGGGAACAGGGGAAAUCCAGAAUAAAGACUUGAGAAAGGAACAGAGUGGGUGAUGGCAGCUAUGAAGAAAAAACAGAUCAGAAGAAGAGUCCUGGCACCUUAGGAAGAGAAAGUGUCACAGACACGAGGCCUAGGCUAGAGAGAUGGUGUAGGUGGUAGCUGCUGUGAAGAAGAAAUGACAACAGGCUGGAGCUGUUCCCUGAAACCUGUGGGAAGGAAGAGAGACCUGCACAGGCCGGCACUUAGCUUGUGGAGAAGGUCCUAACUCAACACUGCAACUUUAAGCUGGCUUAACUUGUCCAAGUUCCAGAUGACCAACAAAGACAGCUAUAGACACUCUAACUCUGUGCCAAUUACCCAAGGCCUUCAGGGCCCUGGGACCUAUUCCAUGAUAGUGGUACCCUAACUGAACCCAUUUCAGCCACUCAGAUUGAUAGGAUGGAAAAGACAGGGCAGGUGGUAGCAGCUGUGAAGAAAAGAGGAAAGCAGAAGGGUGGCCUAUAAUCUACAGGCAUGUAGAGAGGACUACAUAGGCCUCUGUUCUUUGCCCUCAGGAGCCCCCUUCCUGUCCCUUGGACUCAGAAUGGAUCCUUCCAGCACACAUGGCCCAACACUGAGAGUGCAGGAAGCAUGGGUAGGGGCCUCCUGCUGCUGGUAUGUACCCAGGCCAGCCUCCUGCCGACACAGCCUACUGGCUGGGUUCAUGUUCUUACUAUUCACCUCAGGCCAUUGUCUGGGUGCUUAAUUUGACUUGUUUCCCCUGGUCACCAGUCUCCCCUCCGAUAUUCACAGGACAUCAAGCAGCUUCAGCCACGGGUAAGAGGCUUUUCACCCUGCCUGUUGGGUAGCCCAGAGGACCCACAAAGGUCAACCUGAGUCUCCACAGCCUCCUCCCCAGGGCAGUAGGAAUUGAUAUCUCACUUUUGCCAGAUUAGGCUUCUCACUCUUCUUGAGUAGGCCAUAAUCCACCUCUUCAGUAGGCCAUGCAUCUUGUCUCUGCAGUGCCAGAAUUCACAGUCUGGGCCUCCCUUUGGUCCUUACCAUAGGCUGCCAUGUAUUAUUGUCUAUGUUGUGCCCUGUAGGCCUCUGCUAGGCUGUGAACUCCUUGACUGACUCCUCACUGUGUCCUUUUUACCUUGAAUCACAGUGGCUUAUCUAAAAAUAUAAGCUUUUUUCUGUCAUAUUCUGAAUUCCCUGAAGGUAAGGACUAUGUCUGAUUCCUCUCUUUGUCCUCUGCACCCAGCGUAGGGCCUGAAACAGAGUAGCUAGCAGUAAAGAUACACUGAAUGAAUGAAUGAGUCAACCAUCCUUGGCCUCUGGAGCUAAUUGAGAAGGCUAGGGGGAGUUCCGCUGUAGGGAGAAGGAUGUUGCAUCCCUUUGUAGAUUGUGUAGCAUUCAAAACCUGCUGAACACUCACCCUCAAUGUAUAUUCUCUGUUCUGGCCUGCUUCAAGGUCAGUUACACUACUUCCUGGGAUGGGCCUUUCUCUGGCUUAAGCUUGGUUGUCCCUGGCUUUCCCAAGGAUCACAGCCCAAAAGGCACAGUGGGGAAAAUUUAUGGCCUAUUCCAGAAGAGUGAGCAGCCUAAUCAAGCCAAGCCUUGAUUUGGGGUUCUCACUUCACUGGUAUUUUCCCUCUGUCCCUAAUUGGGUUUUCUAUAGUUACUAGUUUUCCAGGCCUCCAAGGGAGAUUCUGAGGCUUGAUGUGUUCUGACUGUGUCUUGGCUUUGUGAUGCUGAGUGCCAGAAAUACUCUGUACUAUAAAAACUACCAUCGUUCUUUGAAACAACAAAGAGGAAUAAAGAACUUAAUUCUGGUGA